AGACAGUUUCUUCCGCUUCCUGUACCACCCGGCUCAAGUAGCGGACACGGAACAGGGAACUAUCAGCCCGUCGGCCUCCGGGCCCUGCAUUCUCUAGCCAUGGACCGGGACCUUUUGCGGCAGUCGCUAAAUUGCCACGGGUCGUCUUUGCUCUCUCUACUUCGGAGCGAACAGCAGGACAAUCCACACUUCCGUAGCCUCCUGGGGUCGGCCGCCGAGCCAGCCCGGGGCCCGCCGCCCCAGCACCCGUUGCAGGGCAGAAAAGAGAAGAGAGUUGACAACAUCGAGAUACAGAAAUUCAUCUCCAAAAAAGCGGAUCUGCUUUUUGCACUUUCCUGGAAAUCAGAUGCACCUGCAACUUCUGAAAUUAAUGAAGACAGUGAAGAUCAUUAUGCAAUCAUGCCACCUUUAGAGCAAUUCAUGGAGAUACCUAGUAUGGAUCGGAGAGAGCUGUUUUUCCGAGAUAUUGAGCGUGGUGAUAUAGUGAUUGGAAGAAUUAGUUCUAUUCGGGAAUUCGGUUUUUUCAUGGUGUUGAUCUGUUUAGGAAGUGGUAUCAUGAGAGAUAUAGCCCACUUAGAAAUCACAGCUCUUUGUCCCUUAAGAGAUGUGCCUUCUCACAGUAACCAUGGGGAUCCUUUAUCAUAUUACCAAACUGGUGACAUCAUUCGAGCUGGAAUCAAGGAUAUUGACAGAUACCAUGAAAAGCUAGCAGUAUCUCUGUAUAGCUCUUCUCUUCCACCACACCUAUCUGGUAUUAAAUUAGGUGUAAUUAGCUCUGAAGAGCUUCCUUUAUACUACAGGAGAAGUGUUGAGCUAAAUAGCAAUUCUUUGGAGUCCUAUGAAAAUGUCAUGCAGAGUUCCUUGGGAUUUGUUAAUCCAGGAGUAGUUGAAUUCCUUCUAGAAAAACUAGGAAUAGAUGAAUCUAAUCCACCAUCUUUAAUGAGAGGCCUACAAAGCAAAAAUUUCUCUGAAGAUGAUUUUGCUUCUGCAUUGAGAAAAAAACAAUCCGCAUCUUGGGCUUUAAAAUGUGUGAAGAUCGGAGUUGACUAUUUUAAAGUUGGACGCCAUGUGGAUGCUAUGAAUGAAUACAAUAAAGCUUUGGAAAUAGACAAACAAAACGUGGAAGCUUUGGUAGCUCGUGGAGCAUUAUAUGCGACAAAAGGAAGUUUGAACAAAGCAAUAGAAGAUUUUGAGCUUGCAUUAGAAAACUGUCCAACUCACAGAAAUGCAAGAAAAUACCUCUGCCAGACACUUGUAGAGAGAGGAGGACAGUUAGAAGAAGAAGAAAAGUUUUUAAAUGCUGAAAGUUACUAUAAGAAAGCUUUGGCUUUGGAUGAGACUUUUAAAGAUGCAGAGGAUGCUUUGCAGAAACUUCAUAAAUAUAUGCAGGUGAUUCCUUAUUUCCUCUUAGAAAUUUAGUGAUAUUUGAAAUAAUGCCCAAACUUAAUUUUCUCCUGAGGAAAACUAUUCUACAUUACUUAAGUAAGGCAUUAUGAAAAGUUUCUUUUUAGGUAUAGUUUUUCCUAAUUGGGUUUGACAUUGCUUCAUAGUGCCUCUGUUUUUGUCCAUAAUCGAAAGUAAAGAUAGCUGUGAGAAAACUAUUACCUAAAUUUGGUAUGUUGUUUUGAGAAAUGUCCUUAUAGGGAGCUCACCUGGUGGUUUUUAAAUUAUUGUUGCUACUAUAAUUGAGCUAAUUAUAAAAACCUUUUUGAGACAUAUUUUAAAUUGUCUUUUCCUGUAAUACUGAUGAUGAUGUUUUCUCAUGCAUUUUCUUCUGAAUUGGACCAUUGCUGCUGUGUCUGUGACAUCUGGUGCUGCUCAUCCCCAUCCACAAACUGGAAAAUGAUUUCCUAUGUAAUCAUGCAUCCAACUGGGCUGUGCUAUUUUUUUAAAUGGUUUGUAUUUGAACAUGGUGAUUCCUCCUUCACUUCACCUUAACGGAAUGUCUUUAUUUGAAUUUUAUUUGUAAAAUGUGUCCUGUUUAAAUUUUUCAAUCUUUAAAAAUAAUUUUUAUGUACUUUUUUUUUUUUUUUAACCUUUCUUGCACUCUGGGUCAUGGGUACCACUGCAAUGGCUUCCCCUUUUUUUAUGGGAUACCAACUGCAAUAUGGUCCUCAAUGCUGUUCUGGCCAUUUCAAUGACUAAUGCCAAACAUCUGUAUGACUAAUUUUUUUAUGUUAAAAAAAUACUGUUUAAUGCUGGCUCUAUGGUGAUUUGGUUUUACUAAAUUGGGUUUCUCGUUGGGGGUGGUCUUUUGAAUACUGGGUUUUAUAUAUUCUGCUAUUUUUAACGUGUGGUUUUUUUCGAUAUCUGGGUUCUAAAAGAAAUCUUUGGAAUUAAGAGAAAAACAAGCUGAAAAGGAAGAAAAGCAGAAAACAAAGAAAAUAGAAACAAGUGCAGAAAAGUUGCGUAAGCUCUUAAAAGAAGAGAAGAGGUAAACUAUAAUAUUCAGUAUUUUUAAACUUAAGGCAACUACUGAAUUGAACCCAAAGUGCCAUACUGGAGGUAAAGUAAAUAAAAAUAUGAAAGUAUUUCAAGUGCCAAUCAGUGACUGUUAAGAAUCUUUAGCAAAUAUGUGUUCCAUGUAUUUUCUUAUUAAAGAGAUGAAGUGGAAUUUAAGGCUAGAAUUCUACAAAAAAAGAGUAUCUUAGAAUUAAAAUAUAGAAUAAGUUACUUUAAUUAUGUUUUAGGAAGAAAUAUUUUAGAACUAGAGCAGUGGUUCUCAACUAGGGGUGGAUUUAUUCACCCGGGGACAUUUGACAAGAUGUGGAGACAUUUUUGAUUGCCAUAACUGAUAGGGUGCUACUGCAUCUAGUGUAUAAUGGUCAGGGAUGCUCUUAAACAUUCUGUAAUGCACAGGUCAGCUCCCACCCGCACCCCCACCCCCUACCAAGAAUUAUUUGGCUGAAAAUACCAAUAAUCAGGUGAAGAAACCAUGAACUAGAGGUAGCCAAAUAAAAAAGUUGAGUUCUCCUUUAUGUGUUCAGUAGUCUUAAGUUUUUAAGGUAGUGUUGAAAAAAGUCUGUCUUUCAGAGAUGAUGGAUUUGCUUACAAUGAUACCUGUCUGCAAGCAUUUUUUCCCCCAAAAGUGCUUAAUAGUAAAAUUAGAUCUUGUAGUAGCCGAGAUUAUUGUAUCAUUUAUCUGAACCACAGCUUUUAUAAAAUCUUUAAAGGAAACAAAUAGGGCCCACAUCUUUAUGAAUAAUUUAGAAACAUUUUUGUAUAUAUAUGACAAAUGAACUGUUUUUUUUAGGCUAAAGAAGAAAAGAAGAAAAUCAACUUCUUCUUCAAGUGUUUCUUCUGCUGAUGAAUCAGUGUCUUCAUCAUCAUCCUCUUCCUCUUCUGGUCACAAAAGGCAUAAGAAACAUAAGAGGAACCGUUCAGAGUCUUCUCGCAGUUCCAGAAGGCAUUCAUCUAGGGCAUCCUCAAAUCAGAUAGAUCAGAAUAGGAAAGAUGAGUGCUACCCAGUUCCAGCUAAUACUUCAGCAUCUUUUCUUAACCAUAAACAAGAAGUGGAGAAACUACUGGGGAAGCAGGAUAGGUUACAGUAUGAAAAGACACAGAUAAAAGAGAAAGAUAGAUGCCCUCUCUCUUCAUCUUCACUUGAAAUACCGGAUGAUUUUGGAGGUAGGUCUGAAGAUCCAAGAGAUUUUUAUAACAGCUAUAAAACCCAAGCAGGUAGUAGCAAAACAGAAAAGCCAUAUAAAUCAGAAAGACAUUUUUCCAGUAGAAGAAAUUCCUCAGAUUCCUUCUGUAGGAAUUCAGAGGACAAGAUUUAUGGUUAUAGGAGAUUUGAAAAGGAUAUAGAGGGAAGAAAAGAGCACUAUAGAAGGUGGGAACCAGGUUCUGUGAGGCAUUCUACCUCACCAGCAAGCUCAGAAUACUCUUGGAAGUCAGUUGAGAAAUACAAAAAAUACGCUCACUCUGGAUCACGUGAUUUCAGUAGACAUGAGCAAAGAUACCGUUUAAAUACAAAUCAAGGAGAAUAUGAAAGAGAGGACAAUUAUGGGGAGGAUAUCAAAACAGAGGUUCCAGAAGAAGAUGCACUAAGUAGCAAAGAACACUCAGAAAGCAGUGUUAAGAAAAAUUUACCUCAGAAUUUACUGAAUAUAUUUAAUCAGAUAGCUGAAUUUGAAAAAGAAAAAGGAAAUAAGUCAAAAAAUUAAUACACCAAGGAUAUCGGCACCAUUACACAAAAUGCCAUUAAGUGAAGUUUUUGGUUGUAUUAGUCAUAACAGUUGAGUGCAGAAAUCUCUGCUUCUAAAAUUAUUUGUAGAGAUUACAGGAAACAAAUGCUUUUAAGUAAGUUUUUCUCAAAUUUUGUUUCAGUUCUAGGUCCCUUGUCACAGCUUGGUUUUUAGACUUUUUAUGUAUAUGUUUAUGUACAGUAUAUUACUCUUGACAGUUUGAAUUUCUUCACCUAAAGAUAAUUCUCUGAAAGUACUGUUUCUUCAUUCUAUUGCGGUAUAUGAGAAUUCCUGGGUGCAUCUUAUUCUGCUGUUUGAGAGAAAAAUUUGUGCAUUGAACACUUGGAUCAUUUUUAUAAAAAUUAAUUUCAUUUUCUUUUCUGUUAAAUUAAAAAUCGUCAGCUUUUGAAAGAUUAUAUGUUCGAAUGUUUCUUGAACACUUUUAUAUUUAUCAGUUUAAAUAUUACAUUUUUUGCCCAAUUUUUUUUAAAAUUUUUAAAUGGUAGAUUAUAUGUCUUAAUUUUCCUCUAAAGCCCAAUUUGAUUAAAAGUGGUUUGUGAACAGUCA